GGGAUGCGGUGAAGGGCGAGCGGCGCGGCGGCUGCGAUGAGUGCCUCUGCGGCCACCGGGGUCUUCGUGCUGUCCCUCUCGGCCAUCCCGGUCACCUAUGUCUUCAACCACCUGGCGGCCCAGCAUGAGUGAGUGAGCCGGCGCGGCGGGGGUCGCGCCGAGGGGCGGCGGGAGUUGGCUCGCCGCGACGGGAGCCUCGCAACUUUUCCGAGGGGGCUGGGACCGUCCGCCGCGGGACAGAGUUCCUGGACUAUUGUAGGGGUUGCUGCCCUCAUCCUGUUCCUGGUAGCACUGCUGGCUCGUGUCCUCGUCAAAAGAAAACCACCCCGGGACCCACUGUUCUAUGUGUAUGCAGUUUUUGGAUUUACCAGCGUGGUGAACCUCAUCAUAGGACUGGAGCAAGAUGGAAUCAUUGACGGGUUCAUGACACACUACUUGAGAGAGGGUGAACCGUAUCUGAACACCGCAUAUGGGCACAUGAUCUGCUACUGGGAUGGCUCUGCUCAUUAUCUGAUGUACCUGGUGAUGGUGGCAGCCAUAGCAUGGGAGUAAGUCAGUUCACCUGGUGUGUGCCUUUGCCACCUUAGCAACCGAUAAGCGGGGAAACUUAUAGAACCAUUGGCCUAUAUUGGGUUGGAUCUAUUAUUAUGAGUGUUGUUGUUUUUGUGCCAGGAAACAUUGUAGGGAAGUAUGGAACACGAAUUUGCCCUGCUUUUUUCUUAAGCAUACCAUAUACUUGUCUUCCUGUCUGGGCUGGUUUCAGAAUCUAUAAUCAGCCAUCAGAAAAUUAUAAUUACCCCUCAAAGGUUAUUCAAGAAGCCCAAGCGAAAGACCUGCUGAGAAGACCAUUUGAUUUAAUGUUGGUUGUGUGUCUCCUCCUGGCAACUGGAUUUUGCCUGUUCAGAGGUUUGAUUGCUUUGGAUUGCCCAUCUGAGCUCUGCCGAUUAUAUACGCAAUUUCAAGAGCCCUAUCUAAAGGAUCCUGCUGCUUAUCCUAAAAUUCAGAUGCUGGCAUAUAUGUUCUAUUCUGUUCCUUACUUUGUGACUGCACUGUAUGGCUUAGUGGUUCCUGGAUGUUCCUGGAUGCCUGACAUCACAUUGAUACAUGCUGGAGGUCUGGCUCAGGCUCAGUUUUCUCACAUUGGUGCAUCUCUUCAUGCUAGAACUGCUUAUGUCUACAGAGUCCCUGAAGAAGCAAAAAUCCUUUUUUUAGCAUUAAACAUAGCAUAUGGAGUUCUUCCUCAGCUCUUGGCCUAUCGUUGUAUCUACAAACCAGAGUUCUUCAUAAAAACAAAGGCAGAAGAAAAAGUGGAAUAAAAAUAUUACUUCAUGUUCCUCCUUUCUAAAUUACUAACUUUUGUUAUACUGGUACUGAUAUUUUGUCCCAUUUCACUCUCUUCUCAUACGUGAGUACUUAAGAAUAUGUACAUUCUUGCUCUGCACUGUAUGUGUGAGCUAUAUGGUAUUGUGUAAAUUUUUUUUGAAGGAAAAUGGAAAUUCUUGAGAAACAGUUUGUUUAAAGAAAUAUAUUCAAAAUCAUUUGUGAAUAAACUUGAUCAUCCAUCUCAAUAUUGUUUGACAUAUAAAAUAAUUAUAAGUGUAAAAAAUUACAAUUUAGUGCCAACAGUAGUGAGCAUGAAAUGAAACUAUUCAAAAGAGAAUAUGGCCUGUGCAUAUUAAAAAAUUCAAAACAGUGAAUGCAGACUGGAGGAGUAACUUUUGCAAAUAAGAUGAAUAUGCUUCAUUAUUAAACUCAAUAUAAAAGGCAAAUCAUCAGAAUAUUUUUAAAUGUUGUUUGAAAAAUGUUUUCCCAAGGAAAGUUUAUUAUUUGCUGCUGUUUCAAGAAAAUUACUUUUACUAAAUUUUUUUGUGUGAAUUUAAACAGCUAAAUAGGGAUCAGUAACUUUAUCUCUAUCCUUAAUGAACAUUUGUUUUAUUGGUGGCUGGAAAUAUUUCUAUUGUAUUUCUGUGUAUAUUUUUAAUAAAAUUAUUUUUGGCCUCUUAUAAAGACAAAUCUUAUUAAAUUUGAAACAUUUCAUAUAUACACAUAAAA